GUAGUAACCCCGAGUCUGCGGAAGUGGUGACCCGUGGGACGCGGCUGAGACAGGAGACUGAAAGGAACCAUAAUUUGUGACAUCAGUUGUUUUCUUUGAUAAGCAGCUAUUUAUGAUUCUGGAAGAUUAAGGCAGAUAGGAAACCCCAUCUGAGAUUUUAAUAAAUCCCUCAAACAAUAAACCACAUCAUGGACAUACAGCUGGACCCUGCCAGAGAUGACCUGCCUCUCAUGGCCAACACCAGCCACAUACUUGUGAAGCACUAUGUACUGGAUUUGGAUGUGGAUUUUGAAAGUCAAGUCAUUGAGGGGACCAUAGUGCUUUUCCUCGAGGAUGGAAACAGAUUCAAGAAACAGAAUAGCUCUAUUGAGGAAGCCUGCCAAUCAGAAUCAAACAAAGCCUGCAAAUUUGGGAUGCCUGAACCCUGCCAUAUUCCCGUGACAAAUGCAAGGACCUUCUCAUCUGAAAUGGAAUAUAAUGAUUUUGCAAUCUGUAGUAAAGGUGAAAAAGAUACUUCUGAUAAAGAUGGUAACCAUGACAACCAGGAACAUGCUUCUGGGAUUUCUAGCUCAAAGUACUGCUGUGACACAGGGAAUCAUGGGAGUGAGGAUUUUUUGCUAGUGUUGGACUGCUGUGAUUUAUCUGUGUUAAAAGUCGAGGAGGUGGAUGUUGCUGCUGUGCCAGGUCUGGAAAAAUUUACAAGGUCUCCUGAGCUCACGGUUGUUUCUGAGGAGUUCAGGAAUCAGAUUGUACGUGAACUUGUGACUUUGCCUGCAAAUCGUUGGAGGGAGCAGUUAGACUAUUACGCUCGCUGCAGCCAGGCUCCUGGCUGUGGGGAACUCCUCUUUGACACUGACACUUGGAGCUUGCAGAUAAGGAAGACAGGGGCUCAGACAGCUACUGACUUUCCUCAUGCUAUCAGGAUAUGGUACAAAACUAAACCUGAAGGGCGAUCGGUUACAUGGACCUCAGACCAGAGUGGCAGGCCAUGUGUUUAUACUGUGGGAUCUCCCAUAAACAACAGGGCCCUUUUUCCAUGCCAGGAGCCACCCGUUGCCAUGUCAACAUGGCAGGCUACAGUUCGAGCAGCUGCAUCUUUUGUUGUUUUAAUGAGUGGGGAAAAUUCUGCCAAACCAACGCAGCUUUGGGAAGAGUGCUCAAGCUGGUAUUACUAUGUAACUAUGCCAAUGCCAGCCUCCACCUUCACAAUUGCAGUGGGAUGCUGGACAGAAAUGAAGAUGGAGACAUGGUCAUCAAAUGAUUUGGCAACAGAGAGACCCUUCUCACCUUCUGAGGCCAACUUCAGGCAUGUUGGUGUUUGCAGUCACAUGGAAUACCCCUGCCGCUUCCAGAAUGCUUCUGCCACCACCCAGGAGAUCAUUCCUCAUCGGGUCUUUGCCCCUGUGUGCCUCACGGGUGCCUGCCAAGAGACCCUUCUGCGGCUGAUCCCUCCUUGCCUCUCAGCAGCACAUUCUGUUCUGGGAGCACACCCGUUCUCUCGGCUGGAUGUUCUCAUCGUCCCUGCCAACUUUCCAAGUCUGGGGAUGGCCAGUAACUGGUAUUCAUAAAGUGAUGUUCUUCUGGGACCCUGAAAGCCCUUGGCCAGGAUUAUUUUGUUCGUCUUGACAAUACCACUUUGUACUAAGCAAGGUAGGUAGUGAGAAUGUGUGUGUAUGUUCCAUUUUUUACAGAGCGGGUAUUAAGAGGAUAUAUAAUGUCCCAAAGUCACUUAGAAGCAGGAAGUCAGGGAGACAAGUAAAAUGGCCUCAUCUUGUGAUGGCUGUCAAGAGUCUGGUGGUCCAGACUUAGGCAAGGCUGAUGUGUAACUGUUUCUAAGGCAGUGAGUGCUUGAUUUAGGGUCUCCACACAGAAACCAUACUGACCCUGUGAGUGAAGAUAUCAUUGAAGAUCAGCAUUCACUGUGGGCUGGCUUUGAGGCAGCCAUAGAAUCUGGAUACCAGGCAAAUUCCUGGAUCACAUGAGUUCUUGGGGGCCAGGCUCUCUCUCUUCUGUUGGAGCAACAGGCAGAGUGAACUCACAGCUUUUGGGUUAACUAGAAUCUUCUUUUUGCCAUUAAACAGCUGUGUUGCUUGUCAGAUCGAGAAGUAGCAUCUUAUCAUCAUUAUACCAUGAUUCUUCACCCUCUGAAAGAUUAUGCUUAAGUGUUUGGUUUUCUUUGAACUGUUCUCCCCACACAAAGACUGACAGUCCUACCUUCAGAGAACACUGCUGGGGCCAUCCUUCAAGAGAAAUUGUCAGGCCUUUGAAAGGCCUUCCUGAAGCAAUCAUUCCUCUACCUGCGUUUGUAAUCUCUCUAUUGAUGUCAUCCUAGGUUCCUAAUGUCUUCCAGUCCUUGAGCCUGAGACGGCCAGUCAGCACCACCUUGCCAUUUUUUCCAUUGCAAAGAAAAGGCUUUUUCCCCCGCCUUGCCACUUAUUUCUUUACCGAAGCAUCAUUACUGAAUAGAACAUACACACUCCCUGGGUGAAAAAGAACAAUGGAGUUCAGUGCACAAAGUUACCUAACUUGGGAUAUUCCCAAUCUUGCAAGCUCUUUCUCCUUAUACCACUACACAGAGUGAGCAAAUACUACCAGCUUCUGUACUGCUGAUGUAUGCAUGUGGUCAUGGAGCUAUGUAAGUAUUUCUUUUAAGGGUAGAUUUCUUUUAGGGAAAACACCAACUCUGGAAAGUCCUCAGGCAAAGUACAAUGUGUGAACAGCUCUGCUGGAGGGAAUAUUGCCAAGAUGCAGCUGGAGCCCACCUCUGCGCCAUAGAGGCCUGUUUGCAUAAAGUGGGUGAGAAAUUGCCUUGUCUCUACAUUUCACCCCUAAUAAGUAAUUGGAAGAGUGUCUCAGCCACCUUUUCUUUUUUCUUUCUUUUUUUUUUUUUUUGAGACGGAGUCUCACUCUGUUGCCCAGGCUGGAGUGCAGUGGUGCAAUCUUGGCUCACUGCCACCUAUGCCUCCCAGGUUUAGGCAGUUCUGCCUCAGCCUCCUGAGUAGCAGGGGCUACAGGUGCACGCUGCUUCGCCUGGCUAAUUUUUUGUAUUUUAAUAGACACGGGGUUUCACCAUGUUGCCCAGGCUGGUCACGAACUCCUGAGCUCAGGCAGUCCACCUGCCUCGGCCUCCUGAAGUGCUGGGAUUACAGGCGUGAGCCACCGUGCCCAGCCUCAGCUUUUCUUUAAGAGAAGUUUAACAUUAUUAUAUUAAAAUGCCACAGAUGUGAGGGGGAUGCCCCCUUCAAAAAUGGAUUACUUUUUUUUAAAAAAAAUUGAAUACCAAGUGGGAGUUGAGGUACAUUGCACAAAUCCGCCCUGAUUUAACCCCAGAGUGGAGCUCAGAGUAGAACAUGUUAUAUUUCUUGGUUAACUAACCAUGCUAUUUAUAGAGGUGACUCCUCGGAAAGUCUAGACAUUGUUCCCAGAAGACAGAAUGCCAAAUCUGCAGUCAUUGAACAAACCAAAUCUGCUCCUACCUUCCCAGCUAGCUUGCUAAGAAUAAUCACCUCCCUGUUUCUCACCAUAAAAUGGAAAUCUUGGAACUUCAUUCUAAGAAAGUGUGAAUGAUAUUUGGGUUCCCCAGCCAAGACUUGGGGUAGGCAAGGAGGAGGAGGUGCUCCUGUGAGCCUGGUCCUACCCACCCUUGGCCUGUGCUCCUUGGAGCCCACCUUGCUAAGUUGUUGGAAACUGUGGUUGGCAGGUCCUAGUUUUUGAGUAGGUCUCCUCUAAAAGGACAUCUUGAGGACCUAAGGAUGGUGCUUUUCUUUGGGAAUGAGCCAGCUGCAGUUUUUGCCUUUUUUCAUAGAUGUGCAAUCUUAGAACAUCCUAUUGAAAGCGCAGUUGGAAAGGGGUGGAUGGACAAAGCCAAGAACUCACUCGACAAACAUGUAUCAACGGACAGGUGUGAUGAAUGCUGAUGAUGCUGUGGCCAUGAGGAAGUAUAGACCUUUAGCCUAAAUCUAAAUUGGGAGUUUCUAAAGUUGGUUUCAAGGAAGACUAGUUUUAUGGAAUGUUAAUAAUGUGGGAAAAGGAACUGUAGGUUAAUUAGUUUAGGAAAUAAAUGGAUUAAAUAAACUUAAAAGAGAUUCUUUACUGGAGGGCUUCUAAGAAAGCCUUUAAUAUUCUUAUGAUCCUGAUUUAAUAUCCUGGUAUAUCUGUGCAUCUUGAAGACAGAGACAGGAUAAGCAGUAUUCCCCCAACUGUUGUGUCGAGGGAGCCCUUUUUACAGUGAGCAUUUCAUGGAACCACUGUGGUUUCAAAAAAACCACCUCCUCAAAACACACUUUGGGAGAUGAUUCUAUUCAGAAAUAUCUGGGAGUCCAUGAUACAGCUGGAGAUGGAAUUCGCCUUUCAUUCUGUCAGUGGUGAGUGAGGACCUGACCUGCAUGCGUCAGGCCCUGGGCAAGGGCUUUGCUUUACAGCAGUGAGGAAGCACAGGUCCUGCCCUCUUGGGACUCACAGUUUGGUGCAGGAGGCCCCCAUGCUUUUCUGUUUAUAGACCUCUUUUUGAGCAAUUACCCAAUUCAUAUAUCUAUAUUUAUUUAUUUAUAAGUUAUAUGCAUUUAGUACAAUGUUAAUAUAUUAGGUACACUAUAAAACACAUACACAAAAUAGAAAAUGUAAAAGGAUGAGAAAAAAACAAUUAUGAAAGUAAAUUCUGUCACUUUUAUCCCAAAGAAUUGGCACGUGCCCUGGGCUCCCUUCAGCUGCCUGGGCCCUACCCUGGAGACUGACUCAGUGAAUUGAGCCGCAGUCUUGGUAUCUGGAAGGCUAACAGGUCUUCCCAGCUGAUUGUGCUGCAGGUGUUGGAGAGCAGUGUGUGUUGCCUGGGGACUGUGUGGACUGGUAUCACCCAGACAGCUUGCACUGACUCCAGACCCUGCCGUCAUGUCACAGGUAAGAAGGUCAGGAAGAGGCUGGAGCGUGCCGGUGAAUGGGUGAGAAAGCUCCCUGGUGAGGCUUCCUGCUUUUCUGUUGCUCAGAAGGAGGCCGUGCUUCCUAGGAACUGCAUCCAGUCACAGGCGGGGACUUUGGGCAAGUCACUGGGCCUCCCUGGCCUAAUUUUCUUCUCUGGAAAAGUAAGGGGGUGAUUUAGAAUAACCCGCAGAAUGUCUUAGGGCCCCUACAUUUGAUUUAAUCAGGGUUUUUUUGUUUUUUUUUUUUUGAGACAGAGUCUCGCUCUGUCACCCAGGCUGUAGUGCAGUGGCGCAAUCUCGGAUCAUUGCAUACUCUACCUCCCAGGUUCAAGCGAUUCUCCUGCCUCAGCCUCCCGAGUAGAUGAGAUUACAGGUGCGCGCCACCACACCUGGCUCGUUUUUGUAUUUUUAAUAGAGAUGAGGUUUCACCAUGUUGGCCAAGCUGGUCUUGAACUCCUCACCUCAAAUGAUCCACCCACCUCAGCCCCCCAAAGUGCUGGGAUUACAGGCGUCAGCCACUGCGCCUGGCCUUUAAUCAGGUUUUUUAUUUCAACAAGGCAUGGGGGUGAUUCAGUUUCGUUCAGCAAUUUAAAAUACAUGUAUAUUUUCUUUUUGAUGUAAGAGCUAGUUAGAUCAUGAGGCUUGGAUUUUCUUGGACUCUGUGGGCACCUAGGCAGUAGUAGGUGUUUAAAUUUUAGGCCCCCAAGCAAAAGUUUCAGAAGGGGGCCUCUUUAACCCUUGUUAAUUGCAAAAUAAACAGAUCUCAAGGGCAGGGGCCCCUUCUUUUCAUAAUAACUGCCUCUGUUUUGUGUGUCAUCAGUGAAAAGCAUCAUUUUCAAAUACUCCAUCAGGAGUGGGUUCCAUCACUGAAGGCCUUCUUCCUUCAGCCCAUCAAAGGACCUCCUCCUUUGACCCCUCAGAGUCAGUGGCUAACCUGCCCCCUACCCCUGUCACAUGUCUUUAGCUUCCAGAUAUCUCCAUUUGCAAGCUAAUAAGUUGCACAUACAUAUGUUUGAACAGUUGUCAGGCUUGUCUGCUGCUCAAACUGUGUUUUAGUUUAAAACAACAACAACAGAGAACUCAGAGCGGGGGAAUGGAUGAAGACAUUUCAGUUGUGCCUGCAGGUGGUGUUGUUUUGACCUUGACAGUCAGUUUUAAAUGACUUGUCAAGUACCAAUGUGUGCUUCUGGGCACACCCACCUGGAAGAUAUUAUGUCCCCUAGGCUUUAUAUGCCCCAGCAGGCAGGCAUGAGGUCCCUGGAUUUUGUUUUCAUUGAUGGAAGGUUAAUGCAUGCAUGGCAGAACUUUACUGAGAGGGGCGCAGCUACAAACCCUGUUUUCAUUUAAUUCUGAUUUCUCUUCUCCCUUGGCCUUUCCCUCCCUGCCCCCAGACCUCUUCCGUCUGGGCUCUCUCCACUCCCCAUCAGCAAUCCCUUCUCUACCACAGCUGCCCCCCACCACCACUUUGGCUUCAAACCAUUUAUCCUGGCUUUGAUAUCUCCUUGCAGAGCUGUAAGCAACCAGGAGAUGCUGGGUCCCAGAGCUCAGCAGGGUGCACUGCCUGGUAGGGGACUGGGCCCCAGUCUCCAGGCCACUGCAGGAAAUUGCACCCAGAAAGCCUGCCCAGGCCCCUGUGCCUGUCCCGGUAACCACUCAGGUGCAGCCCCCAGAGGCGGCAUCUCCUCAGCUUAAGUGUUGUCUGGGGAGAACUUCUUAGGAUUAUUCUAACCUUUCCGAUGGUCCAGGUUCAUCUCUCUGAAUUUUACCUGUUUAAACUUGGAGUGUCUCCCGUACCCUCAAAGGCCACACAUGCUUGUGCUGGCAAGUUGGGGUGAGGAGAAUAAAUGGACAGAUGAAAGGAACCUAUUGGAUUCAUCCUCCUGCCUACCAACACUUCGAUAGUUUCAAGUUAUUUGAGAGUACAAUUGAUGGUCCCUUAUCCAGGGAACACUUCUUCUUCAGCUUCCUUGUCCAAGGAAGGAGACCUGUACUAAUUAGAUCAUGAGGCUUGGAUUUUCCUGUACUAUGUUUCUAAAGGUAGAGAUGAGGGAAAGGGUGCUUGUUCUUAGGACCACGUGCACAUCUUCUCACUCUGUAAUACUUCCUUAAACUUGGGAAGAAGUAGGCCCAGAGCUAGAUAUUUACUUCUCUAAUGGGUAACACCACCAGCAAUGUGCUCCACUGUUUGGUGGGCUUACGGGAACAUAUGAAGGAGAGGGUCCCUGCCUGGCCCCUUAGAUAUCUUGCUGAGAUCUGACUUAGAAUCUAAGAGGAAGACCAGUGCUUGCCAACCUGUCCUCCCCAGAAUCCGGAAGUCUUCCCAAGGCCAUAGAAGUGCAUCACACUGUCUCGCUCCAAGGGACUCAAACCACUUUCUCUUUAUACCCCCUGCCUGAGGGGCACCUCUGUAAGGGAAUCUUAUUACUUACCUUUGGCACACAUCCUGCCCUGGGAUUUCCCAGUUAGAAUGCCAAGUAGAGGAGGCUGAGAAAUGUGUGGUAUGAGAAUGACUGGACCAUGUUUCCUAUCACUGGGAGGAGCCUGGUGUCAGAGAAUGUAGGAGAAGCAGAGUAAGGGAGAGAAAUGGCAUUCACUCUGUGCCCCUGCCCUUCCUAUGGGUCUCUGAGCCUUCAAAUAAGGACUUUAUUUGGUCAAAGCUGGUUGAGUUGAGUUUCUGUUGUUUACACCCACAGCCCUGAAUAAUUUACAAAGGGACACUUCCCUUUUGGUUUUACAAGCAAAAGCAUCAGUUAGACCUUAGGAUUGGGAAGGGGAGUCAGUGGUGUAGACCUAAAAGGAAGAAGCUGAAGCACCAAAUAUAAUUUAAAGCGUUUUAUUGAGCCAAAGUGAGGAUGGCUGCCUGGAAAACUCAGACCCAAGGAACCUUGGAUAUGAGCUCCAUCCUGCCUUUGUUACAAGCAGGUUUUUAGAGGCAAAAAAAAAGGGGACAAGGAGUGGGCUGUACAAAGUGGUUUAUUAGGAAUUCUCGUGGGUUUUCGAAAUAACAUUGAUUAGUGAUUGGCUAUACGUUGUUAAGCUAUAGGGUGGGUUAUAGAGUCUGCUGUGGCAUUAUUAGGUUGAUUUAUAGCUACUUCUGGCAGUAGCAAACAGUUACAAGAGAUGAGUGCAUAGCUCAAAGGGAGGGGUAAGAUGUGAUUGCUCCCUCAUUUUAAUGUCUCUCUGGACCUGAUAAUCUAAAAUAACUCACUUUCUUCAGAUUAAAGAUCUUGGUUGCUUUGAGUAAACCUGACAGUGUCUGGUUUGAUGAAGGUCCACCUCUGACCUUCAGAUUCUUUGAUGAUGAUACCACCUGACUUUAUAGCUUUCGGGGUGUCCUCAGAUAUGUCUCCUCUCACAAACAAGCUCCAGGUCCUUCCACAGCCCUGCUAUCACAGGCUUCCUGUAACUUCCUUCCAGACUAGCCCUGUCCUCCCCCUCACCAGCCUGUGCUAAGACCUGGAAUCCUUGCUACUCAGAGAGACCUCUCUGCUCUGCCCCUCCCAUGAUUUUCCACCCACCAGGAAGGGCAAGCUGUGCUUUCUGGUUCCCUAAGGAGUUUCUCAUGCAGGGUAAUGAGUCCCAGCAGGUGCUGACAGUGGAUCAGGGCCUGGGCUUCUAUAGCUCUUGGCCUCUGAAGCACAGGGCAGGUGGAUCCUAAUGGUGAGUUGUUUGCUUGAGCUGAGCUGCAGAAAUGGGUUGGAGCAUGAGCAAGGGCAAGCCCCAGACAACCAAGAACAUUUCAUAUUCUGCUCCCCAUAGGAUGCAAUGUGAGAUUGAUACUCGAGGGACCUCCACCCUGGCUGUGUUCAGGCUCUUGACACCGCCACAAGAAGGAAUUCAAGGACAAGUUGGAAGAUAAAGUACACACUCAAGAAAAGGGAGUUUGGUGUACUAAAGAGAGAGAGUCAUGCACAAGGGGGGCUGGGGUUUCUAUCUCUAUGGGUUUCUGAACCAAGGGGUGGAAUAUCUAUGUUGAGCAGUGGGGUUAUUGAAAUUAUGUAGCAAGGUAGUCUGUUGGUAAAUCUUUCAAACUUGCAGUUUAAUCCUGAAUUGUUAAUAUAAGAUUAAUAGGUGUGGUUUAUUACCACACAAACACCUCCAAUUGGUUCCUGCUCUGGCCCUGUUGGGGCCUCAUAUGAUGGCUUAAUAAUGAGCCCAAAUCCUGCAAAAUCUUGCUGUACUCAGGAAAGUUCUGAGUUGCUUCUUCAUUUGUGGCAGUCCCACCUUUUAGACAGCCUCCUUUCACUCUGUGGAGAAGGUCUGGUUUCCUGGGCUUAGGAUGUACCCCAGGUAUUUAAUUUUUGGUUUUAGAAAUCUGGGCCUUGGAUGGAGAGACCUGAUACCCAAAGAGGGAGGUUAGGACUUUCCCAGGAGGUUAGGACUUGAAUGGCAUUCUUCUCUGAGUCCUCUUUAGUGGGACUGCAUACAAGGAUGUCAUCCACAUAUUGGAGAAUGACUCCCCAUUUCUAGCUCUAGCUCCUUUUACUCUUGUGCCAAGGCAUUUCUGAACAAGUGAGGGCCAUCCCUGAAGCCCUGAGGCAGUACUGUCCAGGUGUGCUGCUGGGUAAUAUUAGUUCCAGGAUUAGUCCUCUCAAGAGCAAACAAAUACUGAGAGUCAGAAUGCAAAGGGAUACAAAAGAAAGCAUCCUUAAGAUCUAAUACUGUGAACCAGUUGGUCUCCCGGUAUUCGGGUAAGUAUGGCAUAAGGAUUUUGCACUGUCGGACGUAAGGGAAUUACAGCCUCAUUAAUGGCUCUCAAGUCUUGAACUAGACGGUACUCUGUUUGGUUUUUGGUUAGGAAGGACCAGGAGUAUUACAAGGAGACUGACAUGGAAUCAGGAAGCCAUGUUUUAAAAACUUGUCAAUUAGAGGUUGGAGUCCUUGCUUGGCUUUUGGUUUGAGAGGAUACUGACGCUUGUGUGGGAAAUUAUUUUUGUCUUUUAAAGAGGUGAUCACUGGCUGAGCAUAAAUUGCUUUGCCAGGGCUUUCUUGGUCCCAUAUUUGUGGGUCUGAGACCUUAUUUUGGGAUGGAUCUCCUGUCAUUCCGAGGCUGGCUUAGGAAACAACACUGCCAAAAAGGAGGGCCCCCCACCCAGGGCCUGAUAAAUGUAAAGUGGCCUCAGGGGUGGCUAGGAAGUCCCAUCCCAAUGAAAGAGUAGAAUACUGUGGCAUAACUAGAGAUUCAUGAGUUACCAUAUAGUUUCCUAGCCUGCAGUUCAGAGGCACUGUAAAGUGUUUUGAUUUUGGGGUGCCACUGACACCCAUGACAGUGCAGCUUUUGGAAGAUAAGGGCCCAGAGUGGCCAUUUAGGACAGAGUAACUUGCCCCUGUGUCAAUUAAGACAUUGAUAUUCUUAGUUGCCAUGUCAAGAGUCACCUGAGGCUCCUCAGUUAUGAUGACCAGGCCUUUUAUGGGAGCCGCCGAGAACCUCGGGCCCCUUCAGGCCUCAGUUAUGGCCAUUAUGGACUGGGUAUCCUCCUAUUCCUUUGGAGCUGAAGGCAAUCCCUUUUCCAAUGGCUCCCCUGCUUGCAGUGAGGACAGCAUCUGGGUGGGCUCCCCUGGCUGCGACAGAUCUUAUCCCAAUGUCCUGGCUUCCCACACUUGAAGCAGCAACCAUUGCCUGCACGGUUGCUGUUAGGCCUUUUUGGUCCAUGGGUGAAGCAUCUCUCUGGAUGACCCUGAGGUUGCAGGGUGCUGCUCAUAGUAACUGCUAUCAUUUGGGCCUGCCAUCUAUCCCAUUGUUUGCCACACUGGGUCCUUUCAGCCUUUUCAGCCCUGUCCCUAUUACUGAAUACCUGGAAAGCCUCAUCAAGCUUUGGUUUAAUAGGUAUUUGGGGUCUCAAAGACAAUUUCUGUAAUUUUCUCCUGAUGUUGGGUGCUGACUGGCUUAUAAAGUGUGUCCCUAGUUAAAUUUGGCCAGCAUCAGUACUGAGGUGAGUGUUAAUAUAUUUUCUUAGGGCCUUCACAAGGUGACCCUGGAACAAAGCUUGGUUUUCAUCCUUUCCUUAUUUCCCUUAUUUUAUCAUAGUUCACAGCCUUAGUGUACAUUUUUUAUUCUCUCCACUAACCAAAUUGCCAUACAAUUUCUUUUUCUUGGAUUAGCCUGGCCUUGUAGAUAGUUCCAGUUGGGGUCAUUGUUAGGCACAGGCAUGGCCCCCACAGUGUAUAGUUCAGGGUCCCCAGCUAAUAAGUUGUCAGCAUAAGCCUUGGCCUCCACGCAGAUACACUGCUUUUCCUCCAGGGUGCAACAUGUGGACGAGGUAAUAUGAAUAACUCACCAAGUUAACUCAGGUGAGAGUGAGAGAGCCUGAAAUUCGUCCUGAAUUUAGUUGGGUCCUCUAAAAAUUGGCCCAACCUUUGGCUACAUCAUGCUAGAUCAAACACUGAAAAAGGUACAUGCACCUGGAUGGUCCCAGCAUCCCCAUUGGCCACCUCCCUAAGUGAGCAUAACUUAGAAUGGUUAGGAAGGUAGGAAAUGCCACUGUAGGUGACCCUGGCAGGGCUCUGUUCCUUCAGUAGGGAGGGCAUAUAGGUUGGUAAGGAGGUGGGCUAACGGGAGACUAAGGGCUGGAGAUGGUGGAGCUAGAAGAAGACUGGGGAGUUGGAGGUGGAAUUGGGUGGUAGGGAGGAGCAGGGAGUGCUAGACCUAGGUCUGGGUUAGGAGGUGGGGGAAGGCUAUGAGAGGUAUAUUCCCAAAAAGGGUAUCAUCUAGGAUAUCUGGUUCCCAUUUCGUUCUCCUAAAGGGAUGUGAGUCUAACAAAGGCAGCAGUUCCUGCAACGGUCAAGGUUCUAACAGGGCCACGAAGGCCUGUGCACAUGGUGUUUCAGUUCAAUUCUCCUGACAUUGAUAAAAAAGAUCUAAUUGCAAAAUGGUAUUACAAUUUAGGGUCAUGUUCUCUUACCAUUGUACUGCAUUCUGUUUCCUUUUUUUUCCUUUUAGGAUCUCACUUUUUUACCCAAGGCUGAAGUGCAGUGGCACGAUCAUGGCUCGCUGCAGCCUCAUCCUCCCAGGCUGAGGUGAUCCUCCUACCCCAGCCCCCUGAGUAAGCUGGGACUAUAGGCGUGCACCACCAUGCCUGGCUAAUUUUCUGUGUGUUUUUUGUAGAGAUGGGGUUUCGCCACGUUGUCCAGGCUGGUCGCGAACUCCUGGACUCAAGCAAUCUGUGUGCCUUGGCCUCCCACAGUGCUAGGAUUAUAGGCGUGAACCACCACACCUGGCCCUUGUACCCUAUGUUCUAAAAGAAAGGCCUUGACUUGUCUUUGGCAUGAAAUGAAGAAGAAGAGGAAAGUUAACAUAUUCCCUCAUGGAGGGACUGGUCCCAGUAUUUACGAAAUGCUGCAUGGACGAGUGUGGUGCUUACAAUUGGCCAGCUCCAUGGCCAUGCCUGAGAGACAAGCAUCCUUGUUCCCUUGGCUGGCUGCCUUAGUGUCCAGGUGUCCUUGGAGCCCUAGCAUUGCCCAGGCAUCCUUGGCUCCUGGGGCUUUGAAAAUGAGAAGGCUUUUGAGGUCUAGUAGGACGAGUUAUGGCAUAAUUUGAAAGCAGCAAGCAUGCCAAUAUCCAUCCGAAUAUUUAUCCUCAAGUAAAAGUUGGGAACAGAAGUGAUUUAGCAUGGCCAAUAAACCAAGGACCUUGAAGGGGCCCCUUAAGAACUUUAGGCCUAGAUUUGGCAUUCCGGAGGGCAGUAUCUAAGAUGCCUAUCUUGCUGGGUCCAAAGAGUUCCCUAAGCUUUCAUGUGAAGUAUGAGGAAGAAGCAUGAGAAGAGAAAAUCUCAGGAGCUGAGUUUAAAGAAAAUGGGAAAGAGAAAACAGUUCCCAGCCAGGGUCAGUGUUUUGGCACAGCUGGUCCCUUGGGAGAAUGGAAGCCUCUUCCUGGGCAAAAGUCAUCAUGCUCCUUGGAAGCCAUCCAGCCACUGCACAGUACAAGCUAUAGGAUGUUACCCUACCACCCUACCAUGGUGCCUCAGACCUGCCACCUCUGCUUGUCGCCCAAGAUGAUGGAGAGAGAGCUCUGCUUUGCAGUCAGUGCUCUAUCCCCAGCUCUGCCGUUGACUGCUGUGUCCUGUUACUCCCUGGUAAGGUGCCAUAGACCACUCAUCUCCAGAACUCUUGUGGAUAAGAUUAUGUGUAGAUGCCGUUACAUCUUAGGUCCUCAGCAGAUACUGGUUCCUUGCUUCAGUAGGCUUAGGAAAAUUUGGUAGUUUUAUGGGUCAAUAAACACAUAAGUUUUGUGGCUUAUUAGUGUGAAUCACAGAUUCUACAGUUCCUAUCAACCCAAUGUCUAAAAUAAUUCUCUAAAAUAAUAGCUCCAGGGAGAAAAUAAAAAUAGGUAUGGUGACUUAGCAUGGUAGUAUGACAAUAUGAAAGGUUUGUUACAGAGUUGUUGGUCCACAUUCCUUACAUUGUACACAUUGGAAUUUCUCCGUUUCAGAAGGAGCAUUUAGAGCAGCACCUACAUUUUUGUUAGGUUUUCCUUCAAGGCUGUAGCUUGAACUUUUAAUAUACAUACUCACUUUUCUUCCCCCCAAAAAGAAGGGUAAAGAAGGCAGUAAAGGUAAAGAAACCAGACAUUAUUUGAUUCAGCUCAAAAUGUAUUUUUUAGUUCCUUUUCCACAUUUAAUAACAAAUAAAGGCCGGGCGCGGUGGCUCACGCCUGUAAUCCCAGCACUUUGGGAGGCUGAGGUGGGCGGAUCACGAGGUCAGGAGAUCGAGACCAUCCUGGCUAACACAGUGAAACCCUGUCUGUACUAAAAAUACAAAAAAUUAGCCGGGCAUGGUGGCGGGCACCUGUAGCCCCAGCCACUCGGGACGCUGAGGCAGGAGAAUGGCAUGAACCCAGGAGGCCGGGCUUCCAGUGAGCCGAGAUCAUGCCACUGCACUCCAGCCUGGGCGACAGAGUGAGACUCCGUCUCAAAAAACAAAAGCAAACAAACAAAAAAAAUAAAAAGAAAUCUUGUACCUGAUCUUCAGGGAUUUGGGAUCCCACCUGGAUUAAACUAGACUAUCCAAGCCCUAUUUGCCUGGCUUCCAGCCCUCCUGGAGUUCUGUUCCCACCAGUUAGACAAAGCUCUCUGUCCUUGACCUCUUUUCCCAUCACUUUUGGAUCAGAGAUUGAGCCUGUCAGCUCCUGAAACAGCUGUCUCUGAUCUGUUCUCAGUAUUAUCUGAGCCAUUAUCUGACUUGUGUCUGAAAGGACUGCGUGAUGGAAACUUCUGAAAGAACCCUCUGUCACCCCACCCGCAUCUUCCAAAUAGAGCCAGAGAGGCCCAGAGUCAGAAGGCUAAGAAGACCAAGUGUGUGGCCAGCAGCUGCGGGGAGCCAGGGCAACUCCUGCCCGCCACUCUUCCUCUGAAUGCCUAGCCCUCUCCGCCUGUGUUCACAGGCCAGCCCUCCCCGGGGCAUACACAGCAUUUUGUAAAUAGUAACUGUGUGUCUUGGUUGAGAUAAUCUUGUAGGCCAGAAUGGAAUGUCUCAAGACACUUUGCAAACGGGAUUUUAUUGUUUAGUUUUAGGGAUAGGAUCUCACUCUGUCACCCAGGCUGGAGUGCAAUGGCACGAUCUGGGCUCAUUGCAGCUUUCACCUCCCAGGCUCAAUCAGUCCUCCUCAGCCUCCUGCGUAGCUGGGACUACAGGCAUGUGCCACCAUGCCUGGCUAAAUUUUUUUUUUUUUUCAUAGAGACGGGGUCUGACUACGUUGCCUAGGCUAGUCUUAAACUCUGAGGCUCAAGCAAUCCUCCCGCCUUGGCCUUCUGAAGUGCUGGGAUUACAGGAAUGAGCCACUGUGCUCAGCCCAAAAGGGAUUUUAAUUUUGCAAAAGGACCAACCUUAAAAGAGCUUUGAAUAAUAAGUUUCUUUAGUGCAAUUCUUUUUUUUUUUUUUUUUGAGAUGGAGUCUCGCUUUGUCACCCAGGCUGGAGCACAGUGGCGCAAUCUCGGCUCACUGCAACCUCUGUCUCCCGGGUUUAAGUCAUUCUCCUGCCUCACCCUCCUGAAUAGCUGGGAUUACAGGUGCCCACCACCACGCCCAGCUGAUUUUUGUAUUUCUAGUAGAGAUGGGGUUUUGCCAUGUUGGCCAAGUUUGUCUCAAACUCCUGACCUCAGGUGAUCUGCCUGCCUUGGCCUCCCAAAGUGCUGGGAUUACAGGUGUGAGCCACCGCGCCUGGCCAGUGCAAUUCUUUUAUGUUUUUGUUCCCCACCUCUGUUCCGAUUUUCCAUUCCUUAGGUAUAGUACUUUAUGAGCUUUUUGUAUUAACCCCCUGUGUUCCUUCAUGCAGAUGCAGGCCAAUUAGACGAUACAUAUUAUUACUCUCUCUCCCUUUUCUUAAAAGGAGAUAGAACACACACCCUAUUUUACACUGUGCUUUUGUCAAUUAUCAUUAUCCCCUAGAUAUAAUAUUAGGCCUUAAAGAGUUUCUCAUUCUUUUUUAUUUAGCUGCAUAGUAUUCUAGUCUAUGGAUGCUCUCAGUUAUACUUUUCCAAAAUAUGGAUCUUUGACUUUUUCCAAAAUUUUACUGUUGUAAACAAUGCUGUGUUGAGCACCUGGUAUAUUUAAAUAGUCAGUGAAUCACAAAGAUUUCAUUAACAUACCUGCCAUAUUGUGGGAGGUAGGGAUGUGCCUGCAUCUUAUUUAUCCUUCACUAGUGCUUGGUAACUGUAGGUGGAACCACAUGCAAUUUCUGUUUGGGGAAAUCUUAAAAGCAGUAGAAUAUCAGCACUUUUGCGUAGCUCACUGAUAUUUAGAGAAACCUACAUGCCAUAGCAGGGAUGGAGAUAAGAAAAAGAAGUCUCUCGCCCCCAACCUAAUGUGUCUUGGUGAAGAUCUUGCUUAUUUAGGUCUAAGACCUUGUUUAAUAAACCAAGUGGAAGCCGUAAUGACUCCUUUUCAGCAAUUUUAUAACGAUGUAGUUCUUCAGGUUUCACUAAUUUUAACAAUUCUAUAAAGUUAUGUUCAUCCUAUUUUCACUAACUUUGGAAGUUUAAAGAGAAACUCUGUUGAAAAAGUAAAUCCACAUACCAAGUGUUUUUAAAUAGCAUGGAGAAAUGCAAUUUAUUUUUCUGGUUAAGAGAAGUAAGUAUUAUUUAUGCUUUUUUGGGCUUUUGGGUUUAUUUAUUUAGGUGGUGCCUUGGCGUUGAGUGAAUGACAUUAGCUGGUGUGGGGACCUGCAGCAGGGCUUUCAGGAUAGAGCGUUCACCCCACAGUUUCAGUGGUGAGCAGGCAAGAGGUUGCCCAGAUCCUGGCCCAAAAGACCAACCACCAGUCUUACAAACUAAAGGGAAAUCAUAUUUUACCACAAUGAGAAAAAAUGAAGGGGAAGGCUAAUGCUGUAUUUUUUGUUAAAAUGGAAGGAUGUUGAGAAGACAGAGACUUUCAGUGGUUUUAAUCUUCAGACUUUGGCAGAGGCCAAGCAUGAUUUGAAUACAGAGAAAGUGGAGUGACAUGACAGAAAGGGAAGUGGAAAGUGGUGGCUUCCAGAAACAACCAGAUGUGUUUGAAUUUCCAGGCUCCUCAAGGAAGAGUGAGUUGAGCUGGAGCUGAGUUGCUGAAACCUUUUUUAAAGACUCAGUUGAACAUCCGUAUGCCCCUGACAUGUAAUUCUAGAGCAUACCACCCAAAACUCAAUUUUAAAUAGUAGGCAGAGCCUAUGCUGCUACCCUGUUAUGGUUUCAUGUUGGCCUAACUAAUCUAUUUUUUCUUUUUGGUGGUAACAUCAAUGGGAGGCAAGCAAUAGAUGUGAUUUAUCUCAGCCUUAGUAAGGCAUGACAAUAAGAACAAAUUCAGAAAAUGUUCUUUACCAGCAUGGCAAGUUUUUUUUUGUAUUUCUAAAAGGCAACCAUUUUAGUGGAUACAAAAUUAACAUAAGCCAUAGAUCUGUGCACCCUGUGUGUGUAAACACACACACACACACACACACACACACACACACACACACACGCAGGCAUUCAGCCUACUGACCCCGCUCGUGGCUGUGUGCUAUAGACACACAGAAAUACAGUGAUCCCCAGGCUGGUUUGGCAGGGCACUCAUUACAUAGAGGGAACAGACAAAGAGAACCAUCAUAGAAGGGCUGAGAGGCCCAGAGAACAUGGCAGACGAGCUGCUGGUCAUUUGUGUCACACACUCUAGCCCCUUUGCAGGGCCCUUUGACCCCUUUAAGGAUGUGUUGAUCUUGUUAGAAGCUGAAACAGCAGCAGGAGGGUCAUUUUGUUGUGCUUUCAAAUGAAUGCCUGAUCAGCUGUGAAAUAGACUUGUGCUUGUCUAGUCUCUAAGACCAAGGGAAAUGACUUUUCCUAAAAAGAAAAGUUUAAGGAAGUUUUUUGUUUGUUUUGUUUUUUAUGGCUAAGCUUUGCUGUUUUUGCUUUAACAAAACACCUCCCUGCACAGCCUAAUUCCAACAGCAGAGUAUCUGAUUACCUCAUGCUGAAUAAUGCACUGUUGUUUAUUUGCUUUGCUACCUUCCAGAUUUUUCUUUUCUGGGCUAGAUAAUCCCAACAGCUUUGAGUUCCGUUUUUAUAACUUCUAUUUUCCUAUUCUUUAGUCAUCUCAGUUGCUUUCUGCUGGAGCAUUUUCUGAUUCUCUUCAUUGCUCGGAAAUUAAGAAGUCUGAAACCAGACACAACAAGCUGGAAAGAUGUCUCCAUAGCUGAUGAUAGGAACUGUUUAUCGAGCUCUGAACUCUGUGCCUCGUGUUGCGCUGAGUACAUGUCAUGUAUCAUCCCAUUUAAGACUUGCAUCCUCUAUGGAAUAGAUUCCAUUUGGGCAUUUUGUAGAUGAGGAAACUGAGAAAAGAGUAAUUCUGUAUCUCGCCCGUCUCCUAAGUGAUAGUGCCGAAAUUCUACCCAGUUCCCUGCCUGUGGAGCCUGCAGUCUGAACCAUUAUCCCUGGUGCCACAAUUUCACUCACCUGUCCCCUAAUCUUUUUUUUUUUUUCUUUUGUGAGAUGGAGUUUCGCUCUUGUUGCCCAGGCUGGAGUGCAAUGGCGCAAUCUCGGCUCAUCGCAACUUCCGCCUCUUGGGUUCAAGUGAUUCUCCUGCCUUAGCCUCCUGAGUAGCUGGGAUUACAGGCAUGUGCCACCACACCCAGCUAAUUUUGUAUUUUUAGUAGGGACGGGGUUUCUCCGUGUUGGUCAGUCUGGUCUUCAACUCCUGACCUCAGGUGAUCUGCCCACCUCAGCCUCCCAAAGUGCUGGGAUUACAGGCGUGAGCCACCGUGCCUGGCUUAUAUGAAAUGCUAACAGCUGUACUGGGCAGUUGACUCGCUUUCUAUUUAAAGGUCAGUAUACCUCUCUACCUUUUACUCCUUUAUUAACACAUGGUUAGUCAUGCCUUCCUUCAGACUAGUCUGCAUGUCCUUCUGGAAAUUCAUUUUGUUGAACCACUUUUCCAGAUUCUUUGAAUCUCACUGAAUUCUAAUUUGGUCCUUCUAGAGCAUGUUCACCUCCUGUAGCUUGAUUCUCUGGAGCAUCUAAUGAAGUCUCUUAACUGGCAAGCCUCCUGGGGGCUUUUAGGUGUCCACUGCCCUUUGUGAUGUCAUCCUUCACACUUACCUUGGCUCUUCCCCGGGUUCCCACACCAGGCUGAGUGGAAGGAGGUGUAGAUUGAGCAAGCUGUCUGGGAGCGUGAAUUUUUAGGUAGUAGCUAUCUUUUCAAAUUUGGAGAAUUCGUCAGAGUUUUACAAUAGCCUCAGAAGUAGGGAAAUCUCACUUAGAUUUUGUUUCAAGUCCACAGUUAUCGGGUGCUCAUUGCUAUCACUGAGAACCCUAGGCAUUGCCAAGCUAUCACUUUGUGGAAGCCAUGCCUUUGGAGUGAAAACACCAUCUAUGAAAGAUAGUCACGUGACGUUGAAUUGUAUCACACCCAGCUUACUAUGCAGUCCCUGGCAUGGAAGUGACCCUUUGCUACUAUUUAUUAAAUGAGAGAAAGAAGGGAUAUAGAAAUAGGAAUCGCAGUGGUGAUUAAAGUUAUUUUGCUUUUUGCUGAAGACCUCUAGUGUGAUUUCCCCAAUGUACACCAAUUUAACCAGAGGAGGGUACAACAGGAAUCACCGUGACAGUUAUCCUCCAAAUUAAAAUGAAAGUCAAAAAUCUCUCACAACACGUUUUUUAGGAACAACAACAGUCAGUGUUCCAAAAUCUCCUUAAGCCCCCAAAAAGAGGAUUUCAAGAGCCUUUAGUCUUUAGUUUUGCUUCUCUCUAGUUCUUGCUUCUUCUGUAACAUCAUGGCCCCUGCCUCUUUGGAUACUCUAAGAUGUCAAAUCGACUGAGGAUGACUCCUGAGGACCCUUUGAGAUGAUUACCAUCGUUGUAGGUAUAGCUUGAUGUAUUCUUGUGUUUAUGAAUGCAGAGGUGUUUAGAAACACUACUGGGAAUAUUCUCUAACUUUCAGGUGGAACCAGAAAAGAGAAAAUUUCUGUUCUUCUGAUCAUUUGUCAAAUUCAGCUCGAAACAGGAUCUUGAGUACAGAACAUUUUUCCUGGUUGCUGCAUAGCUCAGUUAAUCUGUAUAUCAUGGGAGUGUGUUAUUGAGAGCAUUUGCAGAAGGGUGGAACCAGGAGCUCAUGGCUCAAGCAGGAAAAUGUUUCAUUAUUUGCAGAGCAAGAGAAUGAAACUCCUGAGACCUGAAUUUCAGGGCUCCUUGAAAUGAUGGAUGCAUUCUUUUAACUUGGUGGAGAAAAAGAACAUAAUAAAUUCGAGAAAAUAACCAUUCUUUUACACUUCUUUUUUCUCAUUCAGUUUUGCUCUUUACUUUUUGUAAUACCACUCUCAAGUCUCUAAAAUACAACUGCUUCCCAUUUGGUGAGUGUUUUUUUUUUUUUUUCCAUUUGACAACAGCAUUUUCCUGUGUUUUUAAUGGCACCAAAAUUAACAUGGCUGUUUCAAUUUAACAGAAACAACUUCAAGUUUUAUAUUACACGCCCUACCAAAGAAUCUUUGAUUUUUGCCCUGGCGUUUCCCAAGAUGUUAGCAUGGCUUUGAAAACAGGGCUGUUUAACUGCUGCUGCAGAAGAGAUGGCCAGGGGAGCACAGCAGAUUGGGGAGGGAGGAGGGAGAGAAUGGAGGAGAGGAGGGAAAUUGGCCUCCCCCAAGUUACUAUUUUUAAAGUUUGCUUGCCUACUGAAUAGCUCAAUUUACAAAUCCUACUGGAUAUGGUUUUGUGCUUCCCCGUUUUUGUUUCCUGUUGAAAGUGUGAUGGAUGCCUUGGUGGAAGACCAGCCCCGCAUCCUGCUGUUUUGCCUGUGCCUCUUUACUUACGAAGGCUGGGCCCUUCUCUCCCCUUGAGAGGGGAGACCCACGUUGUCGAAGGCAUCUCCAGGGAGAUAGCCAGUCCCGGAAUUUCUUAGGAGGUGGGACCUCAAAUCCCAAUUAGAAACACUCCAGGAAACAUACAUCUUUAUUUGUUAAACAAGUAGUGUUGUGUGAGCCUUGGUGAAGACGCUCAGUCGUUUUAAAUAAGUGAAGUAAACAUUCCCUUCCAGGGGAGCGCCCUCCCUAGGCGCUGUCACUUUGAAGCUCAGUUUUAAGGUUUUCAGUUGGAACAUGCAGUGUUCUUUUUUCCUUGGCUUGGGUUCUAGAGAAUGUUGUUUCCUCAUUUGGUAAUUGGAGAGUUAAUAGGGUUCUUUGUGAUGCUACCGUGGAAGAGAGACUGUUUUAUUCCAUUCAGGGACUAUAAUUACAGGGCGCCCAUCGGCAUGGUUAAAGUUAAGGUUGUUUCAGCUUUUCCAAUGUAAACUCAUAUUUCAGGGGUUUAUAACUAGCUAUAAAAAUUUGCUUCUAGCUACAGACCUGGCAUAUUCAGUGUCAGCCUAGGAAUAACCUUUACGUUUUAAAAAGUAUUUUUAAAAGGAUAAUUAAAAAAUUCUGUUUAGCUGUUUAUAACUGUUGUUACAAGGAUUCAAGGAAAUAAAAAUAGCUUUUUCUUUUUUUAGCAAAAACCUGUGACCCAUAUUUUUUUAAUGUGGACAAAGUUAUUAGAUUUUUUUUUUUAUGUCUUCAAAGGAAAAUACGGUGAAAUCUGUGUCAAAGCUAUUUUAAAAGGGUAUUGUUUCAGUUUUCCUUGUGGCAGCGGGCAGGGCACCAGAACAUGCCCUCCUUGUUCUCCGAAGACAUGAGCCUCCCAUAGGACUGCUGGCAAAGCUGUUUCGUCCGCGGGCUUCAAGUUCAUUGUGACAGAACUCCUGGCCAAGGAGUGCACAGCAGCCUCUUGGCAGAUGGAAGAAACAUGACCAACCAUCGUGAGGCCAUGGCCACUCUCCUCUUCCCCGCAGCCCUGUCCCUCUGGCCCUACAUGUUGGGACACAGUGAGCAGCACAGGUACAGAGCUAUAAUAGAGACCCACUGGGGGGACCACAGAGCCUCUUCGUUCCCUUUUCCUGAUCCACAUGGUGGGGAAGGGGAGGAGGGAGUUUGCCUCUCUAGGAAUCUCUCUUCAGCUCGGUGGCAUUUGUUGCAGUAAGUAGCUUUAGGUGGGUCUGUUUUUGUACAUGCUGACAGAUGGGUGUGACACAUUGCACAGGUGAUUCAAAAGUUCUCCAAUAAAACUUUCUUUAAAACUU